AGAGAAGGCUGGCUGAGGAGCGCCUGGACAGCAGCAGUUGCUGACGUUCUAUAUCACGCGCCUGGGGCCCAAGGUAACCCAGACCUUUAAACAAACUGCCGGGCUGGGGGUGUUGCGGGGGCAGGAGAGGGAAAAGGGAGCGGAGACUUCGGGGGUCGCGCGAGGAUAGUGGUGGCCAUAGAGGUGGCAAAUGCGUGAAGGGAGGGAGUAGUAAUCCGAAUUCUAGGAGAAAUCAUAGGAAUUGAAGUCGCAGAAGCAAGAAAAGGGGUGUGAGAGCACAAGCGCGAAAAAGCGUGAGAGGGCGCAAGAGCUGGGUGGACCGAAAGUGCGCUGAGGGGCAACGGCUUAGAGUGGAACACACCGGGUCACAGAAGUAUAGGUUAGGUAGAAACAGAGGGACACUUUCUUCCUGUGAGUUCAUUUUCCAAAAGUGCGUCCUUUCAGCCAUUUUGGAGAGAAAAUGUUGACCCAAGUGUUUUUUAGGAUACAGGGAAAGAACGUCAGAGGAAGCUGCACCAAAGCGAGGCUGCGCAGGGCGCAAAAAAGCAGUCAGAGGGUGGCGCCUUUUUUAAAGAAGUUUCCAUCCUUUCUGUCCUAAAGCUCAGGCCGUUCCCCACCCCCACCGCUCGCUAGCCUUCUGUUCCCAGUCCCCUGGCAUGAUCUGAUCGCCUUUGAAGCAGUCGCAGCUGUUUUCCAGACGCCUUGCUCCUCAGGUCGGGGAGUGAUCUGAUGGCCCAGGUUCGAGAAACUUCUUUGCCCUCCGGCUCUGGGGUCCGCUGGAUCUCCGGAGGUGGGGGAGGAGCCUCUCCUGAGGAGGCGGUUGAGAAGGCGGGGAAAAUGGAGGAGGCGGCGGCGGGGGCUACGAAGGCGUCUUCGAGACGUGAAGCCGAGGAGAUGAAGCUGGAGCCAUUACAAGAGCGUGAGCCCGCGCCGGAGGAGAACUUGACGUGGAGCAGCAGCGGCGGCGACGAGAAGGUGCUCCCUUCAAUCCCCCUUCGCUGUCACAGCAGCUCCUCGCCCGUUUGCCCGCGCCGCAAGCCCCGCCCUCGGCCCCAGCCCCGGGCCCGCUCCCGCAGCCAGCCUGGGCUCUCGGCCCCACCCCCGCCUCCAGCCCGGCCCCCGCCCCCGCCGCCACCCCCGCCCCCACCCGCACCGCGGCCCAGGGCCUGGCGUGGAUCCCGGCGCAGAUCCCGGCCUGGGUCCAGGCCUCAGACACGGAGAAGCUGCUCUGGUGACCUAGACGGGUCGGGGGAUCCUGGCGGCUUAGGGGACUGGUUGCUGGAGGUCGAGUUUGGUCAGGGUCCCACAGGCUGCUCUCAUGUGGAGAGCUUUAAAGUAGGUAAGAACUGGCAGAAGAACCUGAGGUUGAUCUACCAGCGUUUCGUUUGGAGUGGGACCCCAGAGACUAGGAAACGUAAAGCAAAGUCAUGCAUCUGUCACGUAUGUAGUACCCAUAUGAACAGACUCCACUCUUGUCUCUCCUGUGUCUUUUUUGGCUGCUUCACUGAGAAACAUAUUCACAAACAUGCAGAAACAAAGCAGCACCAUUUAGCUGUAGACCUUUAUCAUGGGGUCAUAUAUUGCUUCAUGUGUAAGGAUUAUGUAUAUGACAAAGACAUAGAACAGAUUGCCAAAGAAACAAAAGAAAAAAUUUUGAGAUUAUUAACUUCCACCUCAACAGAUGUUUCUCAUCAACAGUUUAUGACAUCAGGGUUUGAAGACAAGCAAUCAACCUGUGAGACAAAGGAACAGGAGCCAAAAUUGGUGAAACCCAAGAAAAAGAGAAGAAAAAAGUCAGUCUAUACUGUAGGCCUGAGAGGGCUAAUCAAUCUUGGGAACACUUGUUUUAUGAAUUGUAUUGUCCAGGCACUUACCCAUAUUCCUCUACUGAAAGAUUUCUUCCUCUCUGACAAGCACAAAUGUAUAAUGACAAGCCCCAGCUUGUGUCUGGUCUGUGAAAUGUCUUCGCUUUUUCAUGCUAUGUACUCUGGGAGCCGAACUCCUCACAUUCCCUAUAAGUUACUGCAUCUGAUAUGGAUCCAUGCAGAACAUUUAGCAGGGUACAGGCAGCAGGAUGCCCAUGAGUUCCUUAUUGCAAUAUUAGACGUGCUACAUAGACACAGCAAAGAUGAUAGUGGUGGGCAGGAGGCCAAUAACCCCAACUGCUGUAACUGCAUCAUAGACCAAAUCUUUACAGGUGGCCUGCAAUCAGAUGUCACAUGUCAAGCCUGCCAUAGUGUUUCUACCACCAUAGACCCAUGCUGGGACAUCAGUUUGGACUUGCCUGGCUCUUGUGCCACAUUCGAUUCCCAGAACCCAGAGAGGGCUGACAGCACAGUGAGCAGGGAUGACCACAUACCAGGAAUCCCCUCACUUACAGACUGUCUACAGUGGUUUACAAGGCCAGAGCACCUAGGAAGCAGUGCCAAAAUCAAAUGCAAUAGUUGCCAAAGCUACCAGGAGUCUACUAAACAGCUCACAAUGAAAAAAUUACCCAUUGUGGCUUGUUUUCAUCUCAAGCGGUUUGAGCAUGUAGGCAAACAGAGGCGAAAGAUUAAUACCUUUAUCUCCUUUCCCUUGGAGCUGGACAUGACUCCGUUUUUGGCCUCUACUAAAGAGAGCAGAAUGAAAGAAGGCCAGCCACCAACAGAUUGUGUGCCCAAUGAGAAUAAGUAUUCCUUGUUUGCAGUGAUUAAUCACCAUGGAACUUUGGAAAGUGGCCACUAUACCAGCUUCAUCCGGCAACAAAAGGACCAGUGGUUCAGCUGUGAUGAUGCCAUCAUCACCAAGGCUACCAUUGAGGACUUACUCUACAGUGAAGGGUAUUUACUGUUCUAUCACAAACAGGGUCUAGAGAAAGACUAGUCUUACCAGACCACUUACUGAAAAAAAAGUAAAUGAUUAGGCAAGGAUUUUGAAGUGACACACAGACCUACUUGGAAUGGACAAUGACAGUAACACCUAUGUGACAGCUAGUAUCUUGAUAUAAAGAACCUAUUUUAGCAUGGCCCAUGGGUCUGUCGGAAGAAAAAAAUGAAUACUAACCAGUGACCAUUCAACCUUAAGAAAUGGGGAGAGGGAGAAGAGGUUGAAAAUGGUCACAUAAAGCAUAAUGAAAUGAAAAGAAUGCUUUAGGUGGGGACAACGGGAGUAGAAGUGUUCUGAUGCUACUCUAUGUCAUUUGUUUUUACAGAAAUAUCUUGUGAAGUCAGGGAGUAUUCCUUUAUCAGCAAAAACUUCACAAUUGGUGUUCCAGCUGUGGCUGACCAGCUAAAUAGUUUGAAAGAAAAAUAAUAUUUUAAAAUAAAGUUUAAAGAGCUUUAAAAGAAAAACAUUUAAAAAGGAAAAAAUCAUUUUUAAGAUUUUAAAAGAAAAAAACUUUUAAAUGUUGAAAAAAAUUUAAGUUGUUAUUUUUAAAAGAAAUAUUUUAAAAGUUAAAAAUAAUUUUUUAAUUUAAAGAAGUUUCAGAAUUUUAAAAAUUAAAAGCAAAGAAAAUUAAAUUCUUAAAGUUUAAAAAUGUAAAAUAAAUUAAGGAACAAGGUUAAAAAUGAAAGUUUACCAAAAAAAGGAAGAAAAUACUGUUAAAAAUUAAAGUUAGAAACAAAGGAACAUCUUAAAAGUUUCAAAUGAAGGAAAAUAAUAUAAAUAGAUAUUUCAAAAUUAAAGCAUAAAAUAUACGUAUUUAAAAAGUGUUAACAAAAUUACUACUAUAAUGAUUAAGAAAUAAAUUUUCAAAAAUACAGAAUGGAAUGCAAUUCAGAUUUUAGAGAAAAGUUUUAAAAGAGGCAAGUUUAGAAUAAUUCAAGACAAAAAGACAAAAUGUGUUUAAAGACAAAAAUUGAAAAAAUACAGGAAGAAAAUAGAGACUUGUAAAAUAAAAAGAACCUUAGAUAAGUUCAAGAGAUUUAAAUGAAAACUUUAAAUAUUUAAAUAAAGAUUUAAAAAUUUAAGCUUUUAAAAAGAAAAACAGUUACAUAAAAAUUGACCAGUGAAAAAAUGUGAAAGAUUCAAGUAGAAAAAAUUAUUAAAAUUAAAAGUUUAAGAAGUUCUAUUUUUUUAUUUAAGCAUAUUAAAAUACAGACGGGUAUGAAAGAAAUAAAUGGAGGAGACAGGAAUAACGACAGCGGUGUGUGAGUAUAUAUAUAUAUAUAUAUUUUUUUUUUUGAGCUUUAUGUUGAUAUAUCAAUAUACGUUGGAAAAGGAAAUAGACAUUUUAAUCAUUAUCUUACCAUCCAAUUGUGAAAUGGCUGCAAGGCCUAAACACUAACUAACCCACCUUCCCCUCUUGAGAUUCCAUGCCCCAUCUCAUAUCCUGAAGGAAGUCAAAUUACUUCCUAGGCAGAAUCAAUUCAUCUGAGAAAAAUGAAAACAUUAGGGACUUUCCCAUUUAGAACUGCAUUAUUCAUACAAAUUCUUAGCUUCUGAAAAGGGGCUCUUGAUAAUUUGGUGGCUUAGAGAAGUUAGAUCACAGCUGUGAAGCUCUGGCUUUGGUAUUUGAGCCCCAUGGCCUGAUUGAGGAAGUGGCAGGGACCCAUAUCUGAGGCCUUCCCACCUUCCUUUUUCCCUCUUCCCCCUCCAAGGAGAAACAAGACCUUUAAUUUCCACAGUAGAGCAAUGGGUUUGUGCUUGCAGUCCUUCUGCUCAUUCUUUAUUCCCUCUUUAUUUCCUUUUUUUGUCACUCAUGCCUAGUUCCCUGAACCCCUUACUUACCUGGCCUUACCUACAUCUCUGAGCCCCAGCCUGCAGGGCUCCUUCUUUGACUAUUCACCUGGUGGCUUUUACUCCUCCUUCAAGACCCAACUCACAGAUGACUUCUCUGGAGUCUUCCCUGAAUGCUCUAGGCAGGUAUAAAUGAGAAAAUUGUUCCUCUCUUCCCCUCUUUAUUCCUCUCACUGUGCCUCCAAAGUACUUUGUCCAUACCUCGGUGAUAGUACUUAUUCUACUGUGAUUUUAUUGUAGCUUUGUGAUUGUCUGCCCCUCUGCACUGAGCAUCUAAGAACAGGGGGCCAAGCCUUAUUCAUUUCUGUGUUAAUAAAUAUUUGUUAAAUGUGAA